UUUUUUUUUUUUUUUAGGACGGAGUCUCGCUCUGUCACCCAGGCUGCAGUGCAGUGGCGCCAUCUCGGCUCACUGCAGCCUCCGCUUCCCGGGUGCAAGCAAUUCUUAUGCCUCAGCCUCCCGAGUAGCUGGGACUACAGCCACAUGCCACCAUGCCCGGCUUUUUUUUGUAUUUUUAGUAGAGAUGGGGUUUCACCAUGUUGGCCAGGCUGGUCUCAAACUCCUGACCCAGUGAUCUGCCCACCUCGGCUUCCCAAAGUGCUGGGAUUGCAGGCAUGAACCACCGUGCCCGGCCACAGCUUCCUAUUUAAUAGUUGUUCCUGAUUCAACUGACUAAUAAUAUAAUAAAAUAAGGAACUAUACACAUGGCAUUAAAUAUACACAUUUAAUUCUCACAAGUUUCUGAGGUAGGUGAUAUUUCCCUGUUUCACAGAGGAAGAAACAGGCUUGGGAGGCCAAGUGGUAUGUUUAAAGUACUUCACUUGUGAUGCUUUAUUUUGUUUGACAUGAAUUCUCCCAUCAUUUUACUCAUUCUUAUUGAAAUAUAAAUAUGGAAAAGGUAUUCCAGUAGUCUAUGUAGACUGAUUUUUGGAUUAUCUGUCAUUUUGCAGUUAUCUUUGUCACUCUUCCCUUGGCUUGUGCAAACAAUCAAGAGUUGAUUACUUUUUUUUUUUUUUUUUUUGUGAGACAGGGUCUCACUCUUUCGCCCAGGCUGGAAUGCAGUGGCCCGAUCUAAGCUCACUGCAGCGUCUGCCUCCCAGGUUCAGACAAUUCUCCUGCCUCAGCCCUGCAGGUGGCUGGGACCACAGACGUGCACAACCACGUCUGCUAGUUUAUUUAUUUAUUUAUUUUGUAUUUUUACUAGAGACAGGGUUUUGCCAUGUUGCCCAGGCUGGUCUUGAACUCCUGACCUCAAGCAGUCUGCCUGGGAUUGGCCUCCCAAAGUGCUGGGAUUACAGGCGUGAGCCACCACACCCGGCAAUUGAUCUCUCUUUUUUUUUUUUUUUUCCUUGAGACAGGGUCUCACUUUAUCAUGCAGGCUGGAGUGCAGUGGCAAGAUCACAGCAGUGCCUCCAGGGCUUAAGCGAUCCUCCCACCUCAGCCUCCUGAGUAGCUGGAACUACAGGUGUGCCCCACCACGCCCGGCUGAUUAUUGCAUUUUUUGUAUUGUGUUUCGCCAUGUUGCCGGUGCUGGUCUUGAACUCAGCCCAAGUGAUCUGCCUGCUUUGGCCUCCCGAAGUGCUGGGAUUAUAGGCGUGAGCAACAGUGCCUGGUCCUGCUGUUUUUUUUUUUAAACAGAUUUGCACUUUGUUUGUAUGUGACCUUUGGAAAAACCAAACUGUGGAGACUGUUGUGCCACUAAAGAUUUGUCUGAGGAUGGACUCGGUGAAGAAUAUAAAGGCAUAUGCAGAUGGGCUCCCUUAGGAUUUUCGUAUAAUAAGAUGUAAAUUAUUGGCAAUGAGUUGAUCAUUACUGGAGCUGGGUGAUGAGUACAUGGAGGUUUAUUAUUCUGUUGACUUUUACAUGUUUAAAUUUUUCAGAAUAAAAAGUUUUUUCAACAAGGCCCUUUAUAUGUAAGUUCACGUGUGCUUGCUCUCUUCCUAGCAAAUUCUAUCAAAAUCCUGUACUCAAGGGUUCAACUCAAAUUCUGCUUAGCUGUGAAGCAUUUUCUGACCACCCCAUAUGAAAAUGAUCUUUUUUUUUUUUUUUUUUUUUUGAGACAGGGUCUUGCUCUGUCGCCCAAGAGUGCAAUGGCAUGAUCUCCGCUCACAGCAACCUCCGCCUCCUGGGUUCAAGCGAUUCUUGUGCCUCAGCCUCCCGAGUAGCUGGGAUUACAGGCGUGUACCACCAUGCCCGGCUAAUUUUUUUGUAUUUUUAGUAGAGAUGGGAUUUCACCAUGUUAGCCAGGAUGGUCUUGAUCUCCUGACCUCAGGUGAUCCUCCCGCCUCAGCCUCCCAAAGUGCUGGGAUUAUAGGUGUGAGCCACUGUGCCCGGCGAUCUUUUUAUUUUUAAUACUUACAGUUCUGUCUGCAUAAUUCCUUCCUUAUCUCAUGUAAAUGCCUAAUCUAACUAUAUUGUAAACUCCUUGAGAGUAAGGACCAUAUGACACUAACCUUGGUUCUCCCAUAGUGCCUAGCACAUUGUAGUACACAUAGACCCUACUGAGUAAAUACCAAGUGGUAAAUAUGACACUGAAUUUCAGGAUGGUUCAUCCUUUGUUGAAAGAAUAUUAAACAUAAGGAGGAUGCUACUGAGUGAAAAAUAAGUGUUUAUAACCCAAGUACUUAUCAAAGAGGGCUUUUUGUAACUUGGUUUCCUGAUGUACCAGUGCUGCAAGAAUGAGGAAUGCCAUCCUUUAUUAAAGUUCUAAAUAAAAGCUAUUAACAGAAUAAAUUGAAAUAAUUGGUAGUAACAUCAGAAUCUUUAUCACAAUUUAACUACAAGAUUCUCCUUAUAGCCUUUUUUCUCACAUACACUGAGGAAGUAAAAGAAUGCAUGUGAAAACACAGAUUGAAUGUGCUAACUAGACUUUUAUUAAUUUGAGAAAAACACCUUUCUUCCUGUAUAUUUAUGAGCAGUUUUAGUGUAAGUUCUGUGAGAAACGGGAACUCGUCUCUUGAUGAAGCAAAAUGUGGUACUUAUAUAUAACUGGUAUUGAACCCCUGCUCAACAUUACUAAUGUUGGUGUGAGGGAAAAGGAAGUCAAUUUAUUUGAACUCCUUCAAGUGAAUUUUGUUACCAAAAUACUAUCAUAAUAACUUGUGUAUUUUCUAUGUGAUAGAGUUUUACGAGCAUUGCUAAGUAAGGAAAUUGAGGCUCAAAGCAUGUAAGUAACUUGCCCAAGGAUGUAAAUGGUAAAGGGCUCAAAGGGAAGAUUAUCUGACACAAAUUCUGACACUGAAUCUGUCCACUUAAUGUUUCCACAGUGUUGACUGUAAGCCAGCCCUCUUUUGCUUGAGUUCCUGUAUUAGCCUCUUUGCUGGGUUUCUUCCAUUAUCUACCUGUUGGUACCUUCUUGGCCUUCUAACAACCUAAGUCAGAUCUUGGCAGUUCUCUGCUUAAAAGUAUGGGUUUUGGCCACACUUAGAAUAAAACCCAGAUUCCUUAGUGUGGUUCUUCAUGGUUUGAUCUUGUGUGUGUCUCUCUGAGGGAUGACAGACGAUAAACAAAAUAAGCUACAUAAGGAUAAAACCCUUUCUGUUUUUGGUACUCUCUCCAGUGCCUGGCAUUUAAUAGAUAUAAAUAGGUGGCUGCUCUGUGCUACCCAUCUUUUUUUUUUUUUUUUUUUUUAAAAAAAAAAAAAAAAAACAGAGUCUUGCUCUGUCCAGGCUGGAGUGUGGUGGCACGAUCUCGACUCACUGCAACCUCCGCUUCCCAGGCUCGAGCAAUUCUCGUGUCUCAGUCUCCUGAGUAGAUGGGACUACAGGCAGGCUCCACCAUGCCCAGCUAAUUUUUUGUAGACAUGAGGUUUUGCCAUAUUGGCCAGGUUGGUCUCGAACUCCUGACUUCAAGCAAUCCACCCACCUCGGCCUCCCAAAGUGCUGGUAUUAUAGGCAUGAGCCACUGCGCCUGGCCCGUGCUACUCAUUUUAAGGCUUUCUAAUCUCAGGGCUGUAUUAUAUUGAGGUGAUGUAUUGUUGUGAUAAUGGUCAUUACAUGUCAGGUAUUUGCAAAUAUUAUUAAACCUGAGAAUGGCAAAUAACACAGGUCUCCAUAUCUAGUGGAAGUCAGUUCUACUUUUGGAUUACUGUUGUGUGUUGUUGUAUCUGGUAUGAUCAUAUCCAAUUGUAGCUGAUGGAAGUUUUUCAGAGAGAAAGUAGUUGAAAAUUUGUGUCUAGCAUUAUAGACUUUAGAAGAUUUGCUCAUUAUUAUUAUUAUUUUUUGAGACGGAGUCUCGCUGUGUAGCCCAGGCUGGAGUGCAGUGGUGCGAUCUCGGCUCACUGCAACCUCCGCCUUCCGGGUUCACGCCAUUCUCCUGCCUCAGCCUCCCAAGUAGCUGGGACUACAGGCACCCGCCACCACGCCCAGCUAAUUUUUUGUAAUUUUAGUAGAGACGGGGUUUCACCGUGUUAGCUAGGAUGGUCUUGAUCUCCUGACCUCAUGAUCCACCCGCCUCAGCCUCCCAAAGUGCUUGGAUUACAGGUGUGAGCCACCGCUCCCGGCCCUUGCUCAUUAUUUUAAAAACAUAUUUUGCCUAUAGUUAAAGUACUAUGAUAAUGUUGUUUGGGUGAUGUGUGAUUUAAACUAAAAUUAGCCAAAGUUAACCCCAUGAAUUUAUAUUUAAAUCAUUUUCCUCAAGGUUUUUUAUAAAGCCUUCGGGGGUAAAGAAAGCUGGAGAGUGUACCAUAUCAGCCUGUAAGUAUCAGGUAGUACUAUCAAUUUAAAUGCUUAAUGAUCAUGCAUUUCUCAAAAAGAUUUCUACGUGAUCAUUUAUUUUAGAGAUGACAAAUGCCAUUGGAUUGUGAUGUGUCAUUCUAUAUAAUUGUAUUUUAUUUCAACAUUAAUAACAUUAAUAAAUUAGUUCUCAUCAUUCAUAUCUGUUUUAUCAAACCAUCUCGUGAAAAUUUAGAGAUGUCCUAAAAAGAGAAAGAGAGUGUUGAUAACCAAGUGCUGUUUUAUUUAGUUGGCUGUUUUUGGCAUCUGAAACUGUGUGUGACUGCUGUCAUGGCAGUUCGCCAUAAGUAUAAUUUGAUUUUUAAAAUUCUAUAAUCUAUUUUUGAUGUUUCUAGAGUUUAAUGGUUCCUUCUUAGGAAUUAAAAUACUGAUUGUAUGUGAUGUAUGUAUAAAUUAAGAAGUGUUUGCAACUUUCACUUUCUUUUUUUUUUUUGAAACGGAGUCUCACCCUGUCACCCAGUCUAGAGUGUAGUGGUGCGAUCUCAGCUCACUGCUACCUCCACCUCCCAGGUUCAAGCAAUUCUCUUGCCUCAGCCUCCCAAGUAUCUGGGAUUACAGGUGCACACCACCAUGCCCGGCUAAUUUGUUUUCUGUAUCUUUAGUAGAGACAGGAUUUCACCAUGUUGGUCAGGCUGGUCUCAAACUCCUGACCUUGUGAUCCACCUGCCUCAGCCUCCUAAAAUGUUGGGAUUACAGGCAUGAGGCACCAUGCCUGGCCAACUUUCACUUUCUAUCAUGUAUUUUCUUAUCCUUACUUAAAGAGUUAGAGGCAGAAUACUUGUCUUCUGGAAUUUUAACGUCUGAGGUGCUCAGAGGGGCUCUAAAUGAUCAAAUUCAGUUUUACAGGGAAAAAUCUAGUUAGUCCCAAUGAUCCUCUCAAUGAAUUGUUACCCCUCAGAUUUUAUUAAUAAGUCAAACUAGGGCCACAGCUUGAAAUGAAACAGCUCCACCUCAUUGUUGUGGAACGACUAGGUUGAGCUCCUAAGAAAAAGUUUUUGUAGGUAUCUUUAAGGUAUUAGACUAAGGAGUAUGCCUUAGCCUAAUAGAGACCUUAUGGAAAAUCCCAUUUCUUGGUUUGUAGGGUAUUCCCUAACCUGGUAGGAAAACUUAGUUAUCUCUCUUUUGGAGUUCCAGCAUGGAUAGUGAAGAACCACCAAAGGAUUUUUUUUUUUAAGUGCUCUGAAGUGGAGAUGUAUCCUAGUUGUUUCUACAUAUUUUGAAUUGUAUCGAAUAUAAGUGAUUAUUCAAAAAGUAUUCAGUUGUGUUAUGCCACUCAUUAAAUUUUCAUUUGAAAUCUUGAGAUAUGAGCACCUCAUUCUGUUACGGUUUCUUCGAAUCAGGAAAUCUUUAGCGUGAGGGUGGUUUUCAUCUCUAGUUGACUGUGACCUAGCCAUGUCUUAGUCCUAGUGUUGUAUUUGGUACAAUAGUUAUGCCUGUUGUACUCCACAGGGUCGUUGUGAGGAUUUAGUGAGAUAAUGCACAUAAAAAUGCUUCAUGCAUUGCAAAGUGCUCCGUGAAAGCACGCUGUUUGUUCUGUACAUUAUUUGUUAGAGCCAGAUAGGUUCCAGAUAGAGUUCCUCACUAUAGAAAUGACUUCUCUUGUUUCACAAUUUAGCCAGCGCUUAAACUUUGAGAUGUCCUUUAUAUUGAGGAUGCCACAUAAUGCUAUAUAAAAAGAAAUAAUAGUCUCCAAAUUGUCACUGAUUUCUAAGUUUCAUAGUCCAUGGCUACAUUCCACAAGAAGAAAGAUGAUGAAUAAAGCUAUGUUUCUUUUUUUUUUUUUUGAGAUGGAGUUUCGCUCUUGUCACCCAGGCUGGAGUACAGUGGCGCGAUCUUGGCUCACUGCAACCUCUACCUCCUGGGUUCAAGCGAUUCUCCUGCCUCAGCCUCCAAAGUAGCUGGGUUUAUAGCUGCGCGCCAAUACACGCGGCUAAUUUUGUAUUUUUUGUAGAGACGGAGUUUCACCGAGUUGGCCAGGCUGAUCUCCAACUCCUGAUCUCAGGUGAUCCACCCACCUCUGCCUCCCAAAGUGCUGGGAUUACAGGCGUGAGCCACCAUGCCCGACCUGUUUUUUCAUGUUAGUUUUAUCUUGAUUUUGAAGACAGUUUCCUUCAUGAUCUACUUAAAUGAAGAAAGAACAGUAGAGUGGAUGAUCCUCAUCUUUCCCUGCUUUUCCUUGGAAUGCAUGGUACGGUUUUCUACCCUUCUAAAAAUGCCUGAGGAGGAGCUGUUAGCAGGUUUGUUUGUUUGUUUGUUUGUUUGUUUGAGACGGACUCUCACUCUGUUGCCCGGGCUGGAGUGCGGUGGCACGAUCUCAGCUCACUGCAGCCUCCACCUCCCGGGUUCAAGGGAUCCUCCUGCCUCAGCCCCACUAGUAGCUGGUAUUACAGGCAUGCGCCACCGCACCCAGCUAAUUUUUUGUAUUUUUAGUAGAGACGGGGUUUCUCCAUAUUGCUCAGGCUGGUCUUGAACUCCCGACCUCAGGUGAUCCACCCGCCUCGGCCUCCCAAAGUGCUGGGAUUACAGGCAUGAGCCACUGCGCCUGGCCAGUAGUUUAUCUGUUUCCUUAUCCCACACCAUGCCUGACAGGCACACCCACUUCCCUUCAUCUGAGGCCUCAGGCUUGGGCUUCACUCUUGACCUAGAUAGGGCAGGUGUAGCAAAGAAAGUUUUGUUCAUUUCUUCUUCAAGCUAGUUAUACAGUCAUUGUGACCUACGUACAGUGCCUGACUUUGUUUUGUUGUUUAAGUUUUGUCUAGACCUUGUUUAGCUUGACCUUCCAAACUUGACUAAAUCUUCAAGCUUUGCCUGAUAGCCUUUGACUGUAUACUCUGACUUUAUAAACUUAUGAAAUUUACACUCAUUUCUUUUUUGUUUGUUUGUUUUUGAGAUGGAGUUUCGGUCUUGUUGCCCAGGCUGGAGUGCAGUGGCACCAUCUUGGCUCACCGCAACCUCUGCCUCCCGGGUUCAAGUGAUUCUCCUGCCUCAGCUUCCCGAGUAGCUGGGAUAACGGGCAUGCGCCACCACGCCCAGCUAAUUUUGUAUUUUUAGUAGAGACGGGGUUUCUCCAUGUUGGUCAGGCCGGUUGUGAACUCCUGACCUCAGGGUCAUCUGCCUGCCUCAGCCUCGCCAAGUGCUGGGAUUACAGGCGUGACCCACUGCACCCGGCCCCCUACACUCAUUUCUUAUAACCGCUUGCAAAAAUACUACUUUUAGAAGUAAAGAUUAGUUGUGAAAAACAAAUACCUUUGCCACUGAUUAGUGCAAAUGUUUCUAGAAAUGCCAUCUGGGACUAUGGCUAGGCUGGCUGGAACUAGUUGAAGAUUUGAGGUAAGAACAAUUAACCAAAAGGUAAGAGUAUGGAGAGGAAAAAAUGGAAGACCAGAAAUUGAGGCUUGGGAAACUCACAAUUAAGAAAUGUCAGGAAGAAGAGGAAUCAGAAGAGGCUCCAUCAGAGGUAGGAUAAUUAGGAAAGUGCAGUGGCGAUGAAAAGGCAUAAGAGAAUUUUUAGGGGCAGGAGUGUAAAAAGCUACAAGGAUUCAGAGAGAAUGAAGAAAAAGCAGGCUAUUGAAUUUGUAAAGGAAGUCAUUACUGAGAGUGCACUGCUAAGAUCAGAGUAGUGGGGGUGGAAGCCCAAUCAGGGGUAGGUCAUAAAGAAAUAAAGGCAUCUUCUGGGUACUGGCCAUUUGUUUGAGAUGUGAAAGACUUGAGGAAAGAGAAUGGUUGGUACAGACAGCAGGGUCAUAAAGGUCUUCUUUUUGUUUUUUAUAAAUAAGGGAGAUAAUUGUAUAUUUGCAGGCAGGGAGAGAAAAUUGAUCUCGGAAAAAAAUAUAUAUUUUUUUCACGCCAUUCUCCUGCCUCAGCCUCCCAAGUAGCUGGGACUACAGGCGCCCGCCGCCACGCCUGGAUAAUUUUUUGUAUUUUUAGUAGAGACAGGGUUUCACUGUGUUAGCCAGGAUGGUCUCGAUCUCCUGACCUCAUGAUCCGCCCACCUCGGCCUCCCAAAGUGCUGGGAUUACAGGCGUGAGCCACUGCACCUGACCCAGUAUUUUUUUUUACUGUAGUUUCAGUUUAGAGAUUUCUACCUUUUAAAGAAUUAUUAAGGGUUUCAGUUAGGGGUUGUAAAGAGAAUUUCAGAGGAGUCCUUAGUGUGUACGUUUAGUUUUUGUCUCUCUUGGUUUGUAUAUUGUCCACUAAAUUUUGGGUUGUAUUUUUUUUUUUUUUUUUCCCGAGACAGAGUCUUGCUCUGUCACCCAGGCUGGAGUGCAGUGGCACCAUCUCGGCUCACUGCAACCUCUGCCUACCGGGUUCACGCCAUUCUCCUGCCUCAGCCUCCCGAGUAGCUGGGACUACAGGCGCCUGCCACCAUGCCCGGCUAAUUUUUUGUAUUUUUAGUAGAGACGGGGUUUCACCGUGUUAGCCAGGAUGGUCUCGAUCUCCUGACCUUGUGAUGCACCCGCCUUGGUCUCCCAAAGUGCUGGGAUUACAGGCGUGAGCCACCGCGCCUGGCCUCUAAUUUUGGGUUGUAUCGUAUUUUAAUAGCCUUUGUGUUUUUUAUUGUUGGAAUAUAAAAUCUACCCUCUACAAUCUGACUUUCAAAACAAUCUGGUCUUAUAACCCUGCUUCCCUAUAUUUCCUUUAAAUAUUACGUGUUACUUCAGCCACACUGGGUUACUUCUGUUUCCUCUUUUAUGUACGGUGACUCUUCUGCCUCGUUUGCCCUUCUUCCAAGUCUCUAAACAUGUUGACUCCUACCCAUUUUUCAAGGUCUGACUGCAAUGUUUUCCCCUUGCUGUGGAGCCUUCUUUCUGAUUGGCGCAGGAGAAAUGUUCUUCUGAUGUCUACAGCUCUUUAUCUGUUCCUGUCAUGUGGGCAGCACUCAGGAUUUUCUGACCUUGUAUUGAAUGUAUUUAAUAUGACCAUCUUCCCGUUUUGACAAUGCACUUUGUAAGGGUAGGUUCAAAGCCAUUAAUUUCAUGGUGCAAGGACCUACAGAUAGUAGGUGCUCAGAUUUUCUUUGUAAAAGAAUGAAUAUUUUAGGGGUGAAAUUUGUUAGAUGCUGGAUUUUAGAAUAGAAUGUCUCCCUAAAAAUAUGGUGACAAGGCACAUGGAAGAGAGGAGAGAACAUCUUACUGCUCUUUGAAGGAAGUACAGAAAUAAAAUGGUUACUGUUAAGUUGGUUCAAGUGUUAUGUCCAAAUUUGCCUAACUUUCUAAUAUCCUGACAACACCUAGAGAAAGAAAGGGACUCAGCUAAGGGAGACAUUUACAAAGGGCCACAAGCCCUUUAGAGCGCUCUUCUUCAUUCAGCUUAGUCUUCUUGAACAUGACCACUGACUCACUUAUAAAAGUAUAAGUAAAAUACAAGUUUAUUUAUACUUUAUAUUUCCCAAACAGCCAUUUAUUAAAUAUGUGGCAUAUAUUACUUGUUUCCUAAAGUGGAGACACUCAGCUGCUUUUUUUUUUUUUUUUUUUUAGAAUUUGCAAAACAGUCUUAGGGAAAAAAAUUUCAGUAACAUGCUCAUGUGAAAAUAUUUUGCAGGAAACAUCUCGAGAUAUGAGUAUAAGCUGUAUGUAAACUAGCUUUUGAACAAUGUAAUAUUUCUCUCUCACUACUAUUUCAGGAAUUCAUAGUCUUUGUAUUACGCUUUUGUUUAAAAAGCUAAAAAAAUUUUUUUAAUAGAAACUUAUUUUGCCGUUUUUUUCUCCUUUUUCUAAAAGUCUGUUUUCUUUUUCAGCUCAUUUCUUGUCCUUUGUUUUAUAAUUAUUCAGAAAGGGCAAUUGAAAAAAAUCUCGUGGCCUGAUGUGUGCUUAUUUUAAAGUUAAUAGAUAUAGCAGUGCCUCAAUCUUAGGUCAGAAUUAAAUAACACCGUCAUCUGGAAUAGGCAUAAACCAGACAUUUGGGAGAUUAGGAGUUAGUUUUGUUUUUGAACCUUUGUAUCUUUGCAGUGGUGAAAACUCACAGGCCUAAGGAUGAUGUAUUAGGCUGGAUUCCUGGGUAGCAAAGGUUAUAAAACCAUGGGCAGAUGUUAUCAACCAGCUUAGGAAAAAGGGAAUAACAAGUAGAAGUAGGGAAGAAAUGUGAAUGGCAAAUGUGAUUGAGCAAUAGAAGCAGAGGCGAAGGUUAGAGAUGAAGUGGAAAAAGGAGGCAGCUACCAGAAAGUAGACAGCUAAACCAGAGUCAUUGUGUAGCAAAGGUGCAGAUGGCCCAAGACAUCUCUGGAAAUCCACCUUUGUGUUCAGGUUAGAUUUACCAAGUUGAUAAUGAGUCAACCUUUAGUGAUAGGAUAGAUAGUCUUAGCUUGUCCUGUUAGCUGUUGAGAGCAUCGGGUUUCGGCUUCACAGCUAGAUACCUCGGAGACAUUCUUGAUUCUCAUCAAAUAAUAAGGCCUGUUGACUUUUCGCUCCGUGUUUGUGUGUAUAUGUAGAAUAUUAUUUAAUAUAUUUUAAAUUUGCUUCCUCUCCCUUUUCCUAAAUUUUUGUUCCAAGAUGACCCUUCCCUUUUUUCCCUUAAAGUUUUGAGGACAUGAAUAAUGUUCAUGUGUUUAUCCUCAGUGGUCUGGCCCAUAGUUUAUUAAAAGUGAAGAUUAUUCUGGAUUUGAUUUUUUUUUUUUUUUUUUUUUUGAGACGGAGUCUGGCUCUGUCGCCCAGGCUGGAGUACAAUGGCGCGAUCUCUGCUUACUGCAGCCUCCGCCUUCCAGAUUCAAGCGAUUCUCCUGCCUCAGCCUCCCGAGUAGCUGGGACUAUAGGCGCCUGCCACCACGCCCAGCUAAUUUUUUGUAUUUUUAGUAGGGAUGGGGUUUUAUCAUUUUGGCCAGGAUGGUUUCGAUCUCUUGACCUCGUGAUCUGCCCGCCUCAGCCUCCCAAAGUGCUGGGAUUACAGGUGUGAGCCACCGUGCCCUGCCCUGGAUUUGAUAUUUUGAAAAUACCCUGAAAAAGUAAAACUUUUUAUUUUAUUUUUUUGGGAUGGAAUUUCGCUUUUGUUGUCCAGGCUGGAGUGCUAUGGCGCAAUCUCGGCUCACCACAACCUCUGCCUCCCAGGUUCAAGUAACUCUCCUGCCUCAGCUUUCCCCAAUAGUUGGGAUUACAGGCAUGCACCACCACGUCCAGCUAAUUUUUUUGUAUUUUCAGUAGAGACAGGGUUUCUCCAUGUUGGUCAGUCUGGUCUCGAACUCCCGACCUCAGGUGAUCCACCCACGUUGGCCUCCCAAAGUGCUGGGAUUACAGGCGUGAGCCACCGCCCCCAGCAAAAUUAUUUUUUUUUUCAAAGUAAGGUGGAAGAAUAUGGGAUGUCUUAAAUUGCUAUCAGUCCUCAGUUAAGAGCCUAAAGGGACAAGCAUUAAACAUCGUUUAUGGUUGUCUUAUGUUAAGUGAAAAACUAUUAUUCAAGGUGUUAGGCUGGACCUACCUUCAUAACAAUCACUAUUUAAUUUGUAGGACCUCUUCAUAACACAGUGGGAGAAUUGGUGACUAUAUCAGUUAGCUAUUGCCACAAUAACACUGCAUGACAAAUUAUACCAAAACUCAGUGGAUUAAAAUAACAAUAAAAUAUACUUAUGAAUCUACAGAUUGGCUGGUGCAACUCUGCUUCUUCCGAUCUGUAAGUUGAUUGAGAUGACUCCGCUUCAAGUGUGUUCAUUUUAGGCCCAGAGUGAAUGGGCAGCAGCCACAUAGGGGAAGCUCUUCUCUAGGCAGUGCCAGGGGCACAAGAGGGCAAGGUGAGACCUCUUAAGGUUUAGGCUUAGAACUGGCACACUGCCAUUUCUGCUCCAUUCUUUUGGCCAAAGCAAGUCAUAUGGUUGAAGCCAAAGUCAAGGAGCCACAAAAAUAAAUCUUACGCCCAUUAGUGGGAAGAACUGCAAAAUCAUAUGGCUAAGGAAUAGAUCCUGGAAAGGAUGAGGAAUUAAUGCCUCUAAUGCAAUCUACCACAGUUAAAGUUCCCUCUUCUGUUUCAAUAGGGCUACUUAUCGCUUUUUCAUGCUCUUCUAAAAUGAAGCAUUUCAUAUAGGCACAUUUCAUAGAAGUCCCUUUCUGUGGCAUUGUGUUUUUCAUUCUGAUGUUUAUAUUUUAUAAAUAGCUUUUGAAAGAUAUAAUUCACGGGCCGGGUGUGGUGGCUCAUGCCUGUAAUCUCAGCAUUUCCGGAGGCUGAGGUGGGCAGUUCACCCGAGGUCAGGGGUUCAAGACCAGCCUCGCCAACAUGACGAAACCCCAUCUCUACUAAAAAUGCAAAAAUUAGCCAGGUGAGGUGGCAUGAACCUGUAAUCCCAGCUAUUUACUCGGGAGGCUGAGGCAGGAGAAUCGCCUGAGCCCAGGAGGUGGAGGUUGCAGUGAGCUGAGAUUGCACCCAUUGUACUCCGCCCUGGGUGACAAAGCAAGACCCGGUCUCAAAAAAUAAAAUAUAAGAUAUAAUUCACAUACUGUACAAUUCAGUCAUUUAAAGUGUACAAUUAAGUAGUUUUUAUUAUAUCUACAGAGUUGGGCAGUCGUCACCACAAUCAUUUUUAUAACAUUUUCUUCAUCCCAAAAGAAACUGUACAUAUUAGCAGUUACUGCUCAUUACCCUUCUCCCCAGCCCUUGGCAGCCACUAGUCUGCUUUUGGCCUCUACGGAUUUGUUCUUUUUCUGUUAAUCGAAUGAUACAUAGCUUUUGUUUUGUUUCUGGCUGCUUGCACUUAGCACAGUGUUUUUAAGGCUCAUCCAUGUUGUAGCAUGUGUCAAUGCUUCAUUCUCUUUAUUGCCAAAUAAUUUUCCUUUUUUAUACCACAUUCAGCUUAUGCACUCAUUAGUUGACAGGCAUUUGGGUAGUUUCCGCAUUUUGGCUGCUAUGAAUAAUGUGGGGCCAGGUGUGGUGGCUCAUGCCUGUAAUCCCAGCACUUUGAAAGGCUGAGGCAGGUGGAUCACCUGAGAUUAGGAGUUCGAGACCAGCCUGGCCAACGUGGUGAAACCCUGUCUCUACUAAAAAUACGAAAAUUAGCUGGGCGUGGUGGUGGACGCCUGUAAUCCCAGCUACUCAGGAGGCUGAGGUAGGAGAAUCACUUGAACGCAAGAGGCAGAGGUUGCAGUGAGCAGAGAUGGUGCCACUGCACUCCAGCCUGGGCAACAGAGCAAGACUCUGUCUAAAAAAACCAAAAAUAGUAAUAGUUAUGCGAUGAACAUUUGUAUACAAGUUUUUGUGCAGAUGUAUGUUUUUAUUUCUCUUGGGUGAAUACUUUGGAGUAAAGUUGCUGGCUCAUAGUUUCUGUUUUUAACAUUUUGAUAAACUGCCAAACAGCUUUCCAAAACGGCUGCACCAUUUUACAUUACCACCAGCAAUGUGUGAGAUUCUAAUUUCUCCACGUCUUCACCAACACUUGUUAUUGUCUUUUAAAUUAUAGCUAUCCUAGUGAGUGUAAAGUCAUAUCUCAUUGUGGUUUUAUUUGUGUAGUGUUUAUAUUUAAUUAAGGGUUUGUAGAGGAAAAAAGCAGUAGUUUAAAAUGUUAGGUCUGAUUGUUUUUAGAAGUGUACUACCAAAGUUGAACCUCUGUUUUAGUCAACUAAAAAUCUUGUGUCAAGAACAAAAAUUUAGUACACCUUUGGUUCACAGAUUUUUCUUCAGGCUACUUCUUAUUUCUUUUGCGUGCUGGAAUAAUUUAGAAAGAAAUUAGCCUCAGAUAAUUGUUAAACUAGUUUCUUCCCUUUGGUUAAGUGAUUAACCGAAUUACUCUGGCAACCUGCUGCAUCAUCAGUAAGCUUGGGACUAGGAGUGGUUUCAUGACUGAAGGUUUGGUGGGUGGAAGUGGCGGUGAGGGGUGCCUUGAUGUGUCAGUUCUUUGCCAGGAGGAUAAUCACUGGAGGAGUUAGUUGUAAAAUACUACCUUUUCUAGAGCUGCACUGCCCAAUAGAAGUAUAAUAUAUGGUAUAUAUGUAAUGUAAAGUUUUCUGGUAGCCACAUUAAAAAGUUUUUUUAAAAAGGUGAUACUAAUUUACAUAAAAAUACUUAUUUCACGCCUGUAAUCCCAGCACUUUGAGAGGCCGAGAUGGGUGGAUCAUGAGGUCAGGAGUUCGAGACCAGCCUGGCCAGUAUGGUGAAACCCCAUCUCUACUAAAAAUACAAAAAUUAGCCGGGCGUGAUGGUGGGAGGCUGAGGCACAAGAAUUGCUUGAACCUGGGAGGCAGAGGUUGCAGUGAGCCGAGAUCGUGCCACUGCAUUCCAGCCUGGGUGACAGGGUAAUUCUGUCUCAAAAAAAAAAAAAUUAUUAUAUCACUGAUGGUAUGUAAUCAAUAUACAAAUUAAUGAGACAUUUUAACUUUUUUUAGUACAAGAUCUUCUCAAUUCAGACUAGCCACAUUUCAAGUGCUCAGUAGCUACAUGUGGCUAGCAGCUCCCAUAUUGAACAGUGCGGUUCCAGAGGUGGUAAAUACUUAUGAUCUAGAUUUUUGCUCACAUGUAUGAUCUGUGUGUCUUUAGGAAAAACAGAUGAGUGUGUGAUCAGUCUGUAUUUCUAGUUCUUUAGUUUUAUAUUGUUACUGCCGGGUUUUCUUUCAGUGGGGAAGAGGGUGUUUAGAGGGUUUCAGAGAGGAAGCUCCUCAUAGCUCAGAUUUUUGGUUGCGAGCAGUUAAAUUCACAGGAGGAAGAAAAUUGCCUCCCUCCUCAUUAGAGAUGUACCAGAUUCUAUAGUUCUCAGCAAGUAAAUCUGUUGGAACUGUUAUCGUUUGGUCCUUGUUCUGAUGGUUAUAGGUGUUCAAGGUCUGCUUUGGCCUGUUGUGUAUCAGUUAUAUACCACUUGUACUGCCUAACCACACAGCUCACUUGGUUAGACAGAGUAAGGUUGUGAAUUUGAUCUCUGUGUUUAAUGAAUGACUUUAUGCCUUUUGGGGCUCUGCUAUAGUAACUAAAAUAGAAUAAACCACAUCCUUUUUCAUCAGAAGUUUAUAGUGUUAGAGACUGGGUGUCAAAUGCCAGCAGAUGUAAUUAAGACAAUUUAGAGACAAGGAGAUUUCAGAGUGGGCUGUUGUAUAGAUUGUGUCUCCUAGUCAGUCAGUUGAUUACUAGAAGGACUGAAUUUGGAAAAAAAAAUUUUUUUUUUUUUUGGCCGGGCGUGGUGGCUCACGCCUGUAAUCCCAGCACUUGGGGAGGCUGAGACAGGCAGAUCACCUGAGGUCAUGAGUUCGAGACCAGCCUGACCAACAUGGACAGGUUAAAAAUACAAAAUUAGCUGGGCAUGGUGGCACAUGCCUGUAAUCCCAGCUACUCAGGAGUGUGAGGCAGGAGAAUUGCUUGAACCCAGGAGGUGGAGGUUGCGGUGAGCUGAAAUCGCGCCAUUGCACUCCAGCCUGGGCAACAAGAGCAAAACUCUGUCUCAAAAAAAAAAAAAAAAAAAAAAGUUUUAAUGUUUGAAUGACUUUACUCACAGCUUACAUUUUCUAAUUUGGCUGAGUCCCCAUCACUUUCUGUUUACUGUACACUGAAUCUCUACCUCACUCAUUUAUGCUGUUUACCUAGCUCCUGGAGGCAAUUGAGUUGUGAUCCCUUAGUAACCAUAGUUGUAGGUCAUUGCCUCAAGGAUGGUUGAAGAUAGGGAUAGCUGAUCAGUGCUCCAGUGACAGAGGAUUAAAAAAACAACUUUUUAUGGGCACUUGCAUGUUUAGAUACAAAUACUUUAACAGGAUUUGACCAUUGCAUUAUUACUGACUAUUAGAUGCCUUAAGGACAUGUAGUUAUUCUAAGUGGUACUCACAUGCUUUUGAGUUGGAGUCCAUAAAUGGUAUUCUGACCAAGAGAACAACGAUCAUGACUUAAUUUACAUGCUAUACCCUGGCAUUUGUGAUAAUAUGGACCCAGGGCCCAUUUGUGAGUUCACUGAUUUGUUUGAAUUUGAAGGCCAUGUGAAAUACUUAUGUGUUGUAGGUCCCGUGCACAAUUAUGGAAUUAAAGAACACCGUAAGUGGUACUAUCUUUUUAAUCAGUUUAUUUGGUGGUUCUGUUGAGUUUUUGUAUACAUUAUUAUUUUGAUAAUUUCCAAAUAUUUUAUACUUUGACACUUGUUCAUUAGCUUCAUUUUUGAAAUGUGUCUGAAAGCCUUAGCCUUACUAAGAAAGAAAUGUCUUUUAGUUGAGUUUGAAAUGCUUUGAUUUGUUGGUAUUACAAAGUAUUAAUAUAAGGGUUUUUUUGUUUGUUCCCAACUGAGUGCAGUCUGCAGUGAUUAAGCUCCAAAUUAGUUGGACCAGUAGGGGCGGAAUUGGAAGCCUUACUUACACUAAAUAAUGCCAUUCCUUUAGGGGAUAAAAUCUGGUUUAGACCUCUUUGGUAACAAAACAAGACCUUAACUGAAGUUAUUUCUAGUAUCUAUUUAUUGAAUAGGUGUGACUUGUCACCCACUUCACACACCAUUGUUACCUUUCUGAAAGCCAAAAAAAAAAAAAAACCCAAAAAAAAAACCCAAAAAAACUCUAGCCAUAAUUUUGAAACAUCUCCAGCCAUAAGGGUGUCAGAUAAGGAAUUAUGAAACUGUAAUACCAUAUUUUAUUGGUGAAAAUAUUGAAAAGUGUAGAUAAACACAAAAAGAAUAGAAAAACUACCCACAAUUCUACCAACACAGAGAGAUCUUUCAUUAAAUUUGUUGCAUAUCUUUCAGGUUUAAAAAAAAUCCAUAUAUUGUGACAGUUGGUUUUUUUUUUUUUUUAAAUUAUACAAGUUGUUGAAACCCAGAAAUCCCAAAUAGAAGUAAAAAAAGAAAAAUCCUAAUUACCUAAUAUUUAACUUACUUAGAAAAUUUAUGGUAACAUUUCAUGUUACCCUUUUGGGCAUUACAUAUAGGAACUGUAGAUCAUUUUUUACACAAAAGCAGGAACAGGUUUAUACUGUGCUUUCAUUUUUAUGUGAUAUUUAAUGUCUACAGAAGAAUAUAUGAUUUGUAUGUGUAGCAUAAUGAACGCUCAUGAACUUCACCAGUUAAAGAAACUAUAGGAUUACCAAUGUUCUGGAAGCCCCCUUUGUACUCUCCUUUGUCCUUCCUCAUGCCUCUGUCCCCUGUCCCCGUUUAGGUGUAACCACUGUCGUGAAUUUUGUUUACCAUCCCUUUGCUUUUUAAAAAAACUAGAUUUACAUCUGCAUUUUUUUUUUUUUUUUUUUGAGACAUAGUUUCGCUGUUGUUGCCCACGCUGGAGUGCAGUAGCGUGAUCUCAGCUCACCACAACCUCCGCCUCCUGGGUUCAAGCGAUUCGCCUGCCUCAGCCUCCUGAGUAGCUGGGAUUAGAGGCAUGCGCCACCACGCCCGGCUAAUUUUGUAUUUUUAAUAGAGACAGGGUUUCUCCAUGUUGAUCAGGCUGGUCUUGAACUCCCAACCUCAGGUGAUCCACCCACCUUGGCCUCCCAAAGUGUUGGUAUUACAGGCAUGAGCCACCACGCCCGGCUUACGUCUACAUUUUAAUGUUUUACUGUACAACAUGUUUUGUUUUGCUUUUUUAAAUAAGUUUAUAAAGAUGACAUAUAUUGUCUUUUAUAAUUUGUUUUUUUCAGUCAAUAUUUUUUCUAAGAUUUGUCCCAGUUGUUGCAUUCCUUUCCAGUGCUGUAUAAUGUUCCAUCCUGUGAAUAUAUAAUCACAUUAUUUAUCUGUUCUGAUAAAUAUUUAGUUUCCAGUUUGAGGCUAUUUCAGAGGAGUCUUGUGAACAUUCUUGUAUAUUUUCCUGGUAUUUAUGUUUCAGAGUUUUCUUAGGGUUUAUAUACCUGGGAGUAGAAUCUACCAUUAUCUUUUAUGGUGAGUGCUUUUUGUGUCCUAAGAAAUUCUUCUCUAGCCUGAAGUCUUGAAGAUAGUCUCCUAUAUGUUCCUCUAAAUAGGAAUAGGUUAGAGUUCAAGCUUUGCCUUUCACAUAGAAGUUUUUAAUCCAUCUAGAAUUAAGUUUGUUUUUUGUUUGUUUGUUUGUUUUUUGAGACGGGAGUCUUGCUCUGUCGCCCAGGCUGGAGUGCAGUGGUGCGAUCUCGGCUCACUGCAAGCUCUGCCUGCCAGGUUCAUGCCAUUCUCCUGCCUCAGCUUCCUGAAUAGCUGGGAUUACAGGUGCCCGCCACCACGCCUGGCUAAUUUUUUUGUAUUUUUAGUAGAGACGGGGUUUCGCCGUGUUAGCCAGGAUGGUCUUGAUCUCCUGACCUCGUGAUCUGCCUGCCUCAGCCUCCCAAAGUGCUGGGAUUACAGUUGUGAGCCACCACGCCCGGCCUCUAGAAUUAAGUUUUAUAUAUCUGUGUAUGGAUUAGUUAGGAAUCCAAUUGUCCCAGAACUAUAUGUUGAUAAAAUAGUCCCUGCUUUCCUCAACGAUCUCUAGCAUUACCUCUGUGAUUGGUUUUAAAAAGCCAGGGUCUAGCUCUGUUGCCCAGGCUGGAGUGCAGUGGUGCCAUCAUAGUUAACUGUAACCUUGAACUCCUAGCCUCAAGCAAUCUUUCGCCUUGGCUUCCCACAGCACUGGGUUUACAGAUAUAAGCCACUGUGCCCAGGUGGAGAUUGUUUUUGUAUGUGUGUUUAUGAAAGUAAUGUUAAAAUGGUAAAUAGUGUUUUGUUAUAUGCUUUUUAAAAUUAAAUAUAUCUUGAAUGUCUUUUGAUACCAUUUAAUAUAUAAUCAGUUUUUGUGGAUACAUAGGAGACCACUGUAUUCAAUCUCUCUAGUUUUUAUUAUAUCACUUUUAUUCCUGAUCUUCCAGUUGCCCUGUCUCAAGAAAGCUUAUAACCAGUUUUCUUUCUAUCUUUCUAGAAAUGUGUGCAUGAAAACACAUGUGUAUACAAAGUCCUAUGCAGUACCCCUGUUAUAUUGCAGUAAAAUACACAUAGCAUAAAAUUGACCAUUUUAAGUGUCACUGAACUCAGUGGCAUUAAGUACAUGCACAUUAUUGUGCAACCUUCACCACCAUCCAUUUCCAGAACUUUUUAAUCUUCCCAGAUUGACACUGUAUACAGUAGUCCCCUCUUAUCCACAUCCCAAGACUCCCAGUGGAUACCUUGAAACUGCCGAUAGUACUGAACCCUGUAUAUACUGUUUAUUCAAUCUGAUAACCAAGAUGGUUAUCAAAUGUCAAACUGGUGGGUAGGGGUAGUGUAUGUAUAUAGCAUGAAGAUGGUAGACAGAGGGAUGAGUGACAUCCCAGGCAGGAGGGAGCAGGAUGGCAUGAGACUUCAUCAUACUACUCAGAAUGGUCCACACUUUAAAACUUACGACUUUUUUCUGGAAAUUUCCAUUUAAUAUUUUCAGACCACGGUUGACUGCAUGGAAGGUGAAACCAUAGAUAAGUUUAAUCGGAACUACUGUACCCAUUAAACUUUUAACUCCUCAUUCCCCUCUCUCCCCACACCCUGGCAACCUUUGUUCUCCUUUCUGUCUCUGUGAAUUUGACUAUGCUAGGUACCUCAUAUAAAUGGAAUCUAACAAUAUUUUGUUUCUUUUUUUUUUUGUUAUUGGCUUUUUCACUUAGAGUAAUGCCCCCCGAGCUUCAUCUAUAUUUAGCGUGUGUCAGAAUUUUCUUCCUUUUAAAGGCUGGAUAAUACUUGACUGUAUGGGUAAGACCACAUUUUGUGUAUCUGUUCAUUUGUUGAUGGGCAGUAGUUGCUUCCACCUUUUAGUUACUAUGAGUAAUACAAUGAAUAUUGGUGUACAAAUAUCUGUUCGAGACCCUGCUUUCAGUUCUUUUGGAUAUAAACCUAGAAGUGGGAUUGCUCAAUCUCGUAUGGCAAUUCAACAUUUAAUUUUUUUCCUUCUCUUCUCUUCUCUUUUUUUUUUUUUUUUUUUGAGGCAGUCUCACUCUUUUGCCCAGGCUGGAGUUCUGUGGCGCUGUCUUGGCUCACUGCAACCUCUGCCUCCUGGUUCAAGUGAUUCUCCUGCCUCAGCCUCCCAAGUAGCUGGGAUUACAGGCACACACCAACACGCCCAGCUAAUUUUUGUAUUUUUAGUAGCAACAGGGUUUCACCAUGUUGGUUAGGCUAGUCUUGAAUUCCUGACCUCAGAUGAUCCUCCCGCCUCGGCCUCCCAAAGUGCUGGGAUUACAGGCGGGAGCCACCGCACCUGGGCAACAUUUUAAUUUUUUGAGGAUCCACCAUUACCAUUUUCCAUAGUGACUGCCAAAUUUUACAUUCCCACCAGCAAUGUAUAAGGGUUUCAGUUUUUCCACAUCCUUGCCAACACUAGUUGAAUUUUGUGUGUGUGUGUGUUUUCUUUCAAUAGCCAUCCUAAUGGGUAUGAAGUGGUAUCUCAUUGUGAUUUUGAUUUAUAUUUCUCUAGUGAUUAGUGAUGCUGAGCAUCUGUUCACGUUUAUUGACCAUUUGUGUAUCUUUGGAGUAGUGUUUAUUCACGUCCUUUGUCCAUUUUUUUUUUUGGCUGGGUUGAUUGUUGUUGAGCUGUAGUUAUUAGUAUAUUCUGGAUAUCAAUCCCUUAUCAGUUAUAUGAUUUGCAAAUAAUUUUUUUUUCCCCCGAGACGGAGUCUCUCUCUGUCGCCCAGGCUAGAGUGCAGUGGUGUGAUCUCGGCUCACUGCAACCUCUGCCUUCCGGGUUCAAGCGAUUCUCCUGCCUCAGCCUCCCGAGUAGCUGGGACUGGAGGCACGUGCCACCAUGCUCAGCUAAUUUUUUGUAUUUUUAGUAGAGAUGGGUUUCACCGUGUUAGCCAGGAUGGUCUCCAUCUCCUGACCUCAUGAUCUGCACACUUCAGCCUCCCAAAGUGCUGGGAUUACAGGUAUGAGCUACCACACCCGGCCGAUUUGCAAAUAAUUUCUCCCAUUAUGUAGGUUGUCUUUUGAUUUUGUUAAUAGUGGCCUUUGGUGCACAAGUUUUUACUUUUGAUAAGGUUCAAUUUUUCUGUCUUUUGUUGUGUGUUCUCUGGUGUCACAUCCAUGAAAUCUGCCAAAUCCAAUGUCAUGAAGCCCUUCUCUUUUUUCUUCUAAGGGUUUUUAGUUUUAGCUCUUAUUUGUAUGUUUUUGAUCCAUUUUUGAGACUAUUUUUGUAUAAUAGUAAAGGUCCAACUUCAUUCUUUUGUGUAAUUCAUUUUUAAUAGGAUAGUAGUGUACCAUAUACGCUGAGAUUCGUUAUCUGGCUUUUUUCACUCAAUAAUGUGUCUCAGCCCCAGUGUUUUUUUUUCAUCCUGUCCUCCAGUAGCCUGUUGAGUGGUGUGAGUCAAUAUGUAGGAAAGCUUUUGAACAUGGCUCCCUUCACUAACAGUUAAAAUUAAAAGAAAAUCAAGUAGGAUUGUUAAACCGAGGAAUGAAAAGUGAAAAAAAAAAAAAGAUAAAAGCAGGGAACAGAGGUGGAGUAUGGGAAUUCCAAGUAUCACCAACUUCUGCUUUUAGGGCAGAUUGCAACUUUAUUGAAAAUUUGUGAGGCACAUUGUUAAACUCUGUAUAUAUAUGUAAGUUUUUUAAAUCCACAUUUGACUGCAUGUGUAUAUAUAUAACUUUUACCUUUAAAUCAGUCCCCUGAAAUGUAGGUGGUGUUUUUCCCAUUUUACAGAUGAAAAACUGAUUACUUACCCAAGAUUUUAUAGUUAAUGAGUGGCACAUGUAGCAUUUGAACACAGGUAUUUUUGACUCUGCAAUUAAUGGUUCUCUGUGAUAAUGAGAACCUUUAAUCAAGUAAGCUUGAAAAAGGCUGCAUAUUAAAUCCCUCUCUUGGAAAUUUGGUCUGAAUUAGCAUAUUAUGAGCUAUGAGAAGUUGGGCGGUAAAAAUCUCUGUUUAAUUUUGCUUUAAAUAUUAAGACGCUUACUUGCUUAAGGGAAGAGUUUGCUCAGCGUGUUAACAAUACCUGGAACAGUUCUCCUUUAACAUUAUUUUGGGAAGUACCACUCACAGUUGCAUUCUAUUUUCUUGUUUCAAAUCAAAGGACAGUAAGUUAAAUCCUAACUAGGUGAAGAAGAGAAUCAGUCCGUAGAAUUCUCUAACACAGACCAGGUGUGCAGCUUUUGGAGCGGGGGAGAUGAGGAAUGUCAGUUUAUACUUCAAAGUCUGCUGUGAUGAUGUAACUCAAAAGUAAUGUGCUUUUCCAGAGGUGAAUUGCAUGUGACUGCAGCUUCCCCUGUCUACAUGACAGGUAUUAAACUGUAGCUUUAUUUUAUUUUAGUUUUAUUAUCUUAUUCUUUUUUUUUUUUUUUUUUUUUUGAGACAGAGUUUUGCUCUUGUUGCCCAGGCUGGAGUGCAAUGGCGCGAUCUCGGCUCACCACAACCUCCGCCUCCCAGGUUCAAGUGAUUUUCCUGCCUCAACCUCCCAAGUAGCUGGGAUUACAGGCGCCCGCCACCACACCCAGCUAAUUUUGUAUUUUAUGUAGAGACGGGGUUUCUCCAUGUUGGUCGAGCUAGUCUUAAACUCGCGACCUCAGGUGAUCCACCCGCCUCAGCCUCCCAAAGUGCUGGGAUUACGGGUAUGAGCCACUGCGCCCGGCCUUAUCGUCUUAUUCUUAACCCUACAAGGAAUGCAAGGCUGUAGCUUUAUUUCAGUGUGUAUGAUAUGGUAAGAUAACACAACAGAAGGAUUUAAGGCAUAGAUAAUUUAAGAAAAAAUAAUUUUUGACCAGCAAUACUUCUUACAUAUGGGCUUUGAGUUUAAGGAUUUUAUCUUGGUCCUGAAUUGUUCAUUUUAGCUCUGCCACUGAUAAACAUAAGCUGUGAUAUAGGAAAUGAAAGAUUGUCUCUAUUAUGGGCGUAUUAUUUAAAUAUUGAACAGAAACUCGUGUCAGAGAUGGUCAGCAAAUGAAUGAAUCAGCAGCCCAUUAGCGUUUAGCUUGUAAGAGAAAGUCAUUUAUCAGCUGAAUUGAGACCCAAUCCCUUGAUUAGGCAUUGCUUUUAGUAUUCAGUAGGGCUAAUCCUAUCUUUAUGUUUUUACAGAGUGUUCUUUGAUAUUUUUGCCCACUUAUUUUUCCAAGUUUUCCCAAGUUCCGUAAAGUAUCUUGUUAAUGAUUUCAUUGGAAAUAUGUUACAGCUGUUACUUAACUGGGACAAAAUCUUCAUGAUAUUCUGGUAUAUUCCUUCUCUGCAACUGACCAAGUUUUUGUUUUUUGUUUUUUGUUUUUUAAAUACUACAUUAAUUACCAAAUAUUUUAUACUUUUUGUUGUUUUAAUUAAGAUAUUUCAUUUUUUUCCUAGCUGGUCAUUACUGGUAUGUAGAAAUACAUUUUAUUUUGGCCUUUACAAUUCCUUUCUUAUUUCUCACUCUGAUAUUUUUAUUUUCCUGUUUAAUUAAUUUUUUUUUCUUUUUUAAGACAAGAGUCUUGCUCUCUUGCCCAGGCUGGAGUGCAGUGGUGCAGUGGCUCACUGCAACCUCUGCCUCCCAGAUUCAAGCGAUUCUCCUGCCUCAGGCUCCCAAGUAGUUGGGAUUAUAGGCGUGAGCCACCAUGCCCAGCCUACACUGAUUGCUUUUCAAAUAUUAAACCAGCCCUGCAUUCCUGAAAUCAUAACGUGUUAUGCUUUUUCUUUCUUUCUUUCUUUUUUUUUUUUAAGACGGAGUUUCACUCUUGUUGCCCAGGCUGGAGUGCAAUGGCACGAUCUCGGCUCACUGCACCCUCCACCUCCCAGGUUCAAGCGAUUCUCCUGCCUCAGCCCCCCGAGUAGCUGAGACUCCAGGUGCCUGCCACCACACCCAGCUAAUUUUUAUAUUUUUACUAGAGACAGGGUCUCGUCAUGUUGGCCAGGCUGGUCUUGAACUCCUGACCUUGGGUGAUCCACCCGCCUCGGCCUCCCAAAGUGCUGGGAUUACAGGCGCGAGCCACCACUCCUGGCCGGGUUAUGCUUUUUCUGUAUGGCAGGGUUUGAUUUGCUAACAUUUUGUUACAGAUUUUCAUGUCUCUAUUCAUGAGACACACUGGUCUGUGAUUUUUUUAGGUCUUUAGUUUUGGUAUCAGGGUAAUGCUGGCCUUAUAGAAUGAGUUGGGAAGUGUUUUCUGUCCUCUUCUGGAAGAUGGUGUAGAAUUGAUAAUUCUUUCUUCAAAUGGUUGGUAGAUCACUAGUGAAGUCAUCUGGACUUGGAGUUUUCUUUGUGGGAGGAUUUUAAGCUACAAUUUCAAUUUUGUUACCAGAUAUUGGCCUGUUUAGGCUAUAUAUUGAUUUAGGGUUUGUAUGUAUCUUUAUCCCAAUUUAUGUUGAAAUUGGUAGUUUGUCUCUUUCCAUUUCAUCUACGUAGUCUAAUUUGUUGUUUGUAUAAGUUUAUAGGUUUUUUUUUCUACCUUUUAAAUGUUUGUAACGUCUGUUGUGAUGUUCCUUCUUUCAUUCCUAGUGUUAGUAAUUUGUACUUCUCCCUUUCUCCUGAUCAGUUUAGCUAGAUGAUUUUAUCUUUUCAAAGAAUUGCUUUUAGUUUCAUUGCUUUUUCUCUAGUGUUUUUCCAUUUUUUUGAUGUCUGCACUCAUGUUUAUCACGUCCUUCUUUCUUUGCAUUUAAUUUGUGUGUGUGUGUGUGUGUGUGUGUGUGUGUGUGUAUGUGUUUCUCAAGGUAGAAGCUUAGAUCAUUAAUUUGAAAACUUUCUUUUUUUCCAGUAUAGGUAUUGAAAAUUAUACGUUUCCCUCUAAGCACUUUUUAGCUGCAUGCUGUACAUACUGUACAUUUUGGUCUGCUUGAUUUUCAUUCAAGUCAAAAUAUUUUCUUUCUUCUUUUUUUUUUUUUUUUUUUUGAGACAGAGUCUCGCUCUGUCACACAGGCUGGAGUGCAGUGGCGCGAUCUCGGCUCACUGCAAGCUCUGCCUCCCAGGUUCACGCCAUUCUCCUGCCUCACCCUCCCAAGUAGCUGGGACUACAGGUGCCCGCCACCACGCCCAGCUAAUUUUUUGUAUUUUUUUUUAGUAGAGACGGGGUUUCACCGUGUUAGUCAGGAUGGUCUCGAGCUCCUGACCUCAUGAUCUGCCCGCCUCAGCCUCCCAAAGUGCUGAGAUUACAGGCGUGAGCCACUGUGCCUGGCCCAUUCAAGUCAAAAUAUUUUCUAAUUUCCCUUAUUAUUUCCUUUGACCCAUGAGUUAUUUAGAAGUGUUUUUUCUUCUAUUAAUUUCUAGUUUAAUUCUCCUGUAGUUAGAGAAUAUGCUUUGUAUUAUUUCAGUCUUUUUAAAUUGAGGGAUGGAGGUUGUGUGUUUUUGGUGGUCUAGAAUAUGAUCCAUGUUGGUGAAUGUUUUAAGUACACUUGAAAAUAAUGUAUAUUCUGCUGUUACUGGGUGAAAUAUUGUAUAAGUAUCUGUGAAGUCAAGUUGGUCAGUAGUCCUUGGUGAUUUGGGUGGGGGGGGUCUGUUUGUUUUGCCAAUCACUAAUCAUUUUGUAAUAUCCCUCCUAAUAUUCCUUGUUCCAAAGUCUACUUUGUUGAUAUUGACACCACUCCAGCUUAGUGCCUGUAUGGUGUAUGUAUUUUCUUUAUCUUUUUAAUCUGUGUAUUUAUAUUUAAACUAUGUUUCUUAUACAUAGCAUGUGGCCGGAUCUUACUUUUUUGUCCAGUUUGACAAUCUGCCUUUUAGACUAGGUGUAUCAUUUACAUUUGAUGUAAUUAUUGAUAUGCUUAUGUUAAAAUUUUUUUCCUUCUUGGAAUUUAUUUUUCAUCUUUUUUCUCCUUUUCCAUGUUUUCCUGCCUUUUUAAAACAUGAAGUAUUUUUGUGAUUCCAUUUUAUCUCUUUUUUUUUUUUUUGAAAUGGAGUCUCUGUCGCCCAGGCUAGAGGGCAGUGGCACAGUCUCGGCUGACUGCAACCUUCACCUCAGGGGUUCAAACAAUUCUCCUGCCUCAGCCUCUGGAGUAGUUGGGAUUACGGGCGUCCGCCACCAUGCUUGGCUAAUUUUUUGCAUUUUUAGUAGAGAUGGGGUUUCACCAUGUUGGCCAGGCUGGUCUGUUCUUGAUUUACUAGCUUCACAUCUUUGUUUUAUAUUUUUAGUGGUUGAUACAGGGUGUAUAGUAUGCAUCUUCAUCACCAUCUAUGUUGAAAUAAUGUUAUACUAUUUCACCUGUAACUUAAGCAUAAUUUUAAAAAUUUUAAAUUUUUUCUAUUUUAAUUUUUUUCUGUUUUAGUUAUUUUCAUGGCAUAAAAGGCCACCAGUAAUUAGUGCCUUAAAACAACACUAUUGCCAAUUUAGUCUGUGGGUUAGGCAUUUGGAUGGGGCACAGCAGAGAUGUUCUGUCUUUGCUUCAUGAUGCCUGUGUCCUCUGCUGAGGCAGCUCAAAGCUGGGGGCUGGGAGUAUCUGAAGGUUUACCCACUUGCAUGUUAAGCAGUUGAUGCUGGCUCAGACCUUAGCUUAGUCUGUUGGCCGGAACCCGUGCACAUGACCUUUUUAUGUGGCCUAAAUUUUCUUACAAUCUGGUAGUUGGGUUCCAAAGGCAAAUGUCCUAAGAGAAGAGAGCCAAAUAGAAGCUAUAUUGGCUUUUGUGACCCAGCCUUGACUAGUGUCACUUCUGCUAUAUUUUUUAGGUGGAGGCAGUUACGGAGGUUUGUCUGAAUUCAAGGAGAAGGUGCAUAACCACCUCCUACCCCACCAGCACACACACACACACUCACACUCACACAUCCUCUCCUAUCCCAAACUCUCCCCCACAUCACACACACCCUCUCGUAUCCCAGCCCACAUGCUCUGCUUCCAGUGUGACAUCGACAGGAAUAUUGAUGCCAUAUUGGAAGCAAGGCAUGUGGGCUGGGAAAGGAGGCAGUCUUUGGAAAAUAUAGUCUACCACACUGCUGCCUUUGUGCUGCUGUUAUCAGGCAUUUUAAUUCUUUGUAUGUUAUGUUACACAAUACAUUAUUAUUUUUGUUUUAAACAUGUCUUUUACAUUUACUCACUUAUUUCUUUUAUUCUUUUUUUUUUUUUUUUUUGCGACAGGGUCUCGCUCUGUCAUCUAGGCUGGAGUGCAGUGGCGCAAUCUCAGCUCACUGCAACCUCUGCCUCCCAGGUUCAAUCAAUUCUCCUGCCUCAGCCUCCUGAGUAUCUGGGACUACAGGCACCCAUCUCCACGCCCAGCUAAUUUUUAUAUUUUUAGUAGAGAUGGGGUUUCACCAUGUUGGCCAGGUUGGUCUCGAUCUCCUGGCCUCAGGUGAUUCGCCUUCCUCGGUCUUCCUAAGUGCUGGGAUUACAGGCGUGAGCCACCACGCCUGGCCAUAUUUACCAUUUCUUUCACUCUUCAUUUCUUUUUGUAGAUGCACAUUUCCAUCUGGUAUUUUUCUUCUGUGUGGAGAAAUUCCUUUAACAUUAGUUGUAGUAGGGUUCUGCUGAUAAUGAAUUAUCUCAGCUUUUAUUGGUCUAAAGUAUUUUGUCUCCAUAUUUGAAAACUAUGUAUCACUGGGUGAAGAAGUUUAUAUUGACUUUUUUUCCUUCAGUACUUUAAAGAUCUCCCAUUUUCUUCUUGCUGCAUGAUUUCUAAUUUCAUUUUUUAAUUAAUUAAUUAAUUAAUUUUUUUGAGAUGGAGUCUAGCUGUGUUGCCCAGGCUGGAGUGCAGUGGCAUGAUCUUGGCUCACUGCAACCUCCGCCUCCCGGUUUCAAGUGAUUGUCCUGCCUCAGCCUCCUGAGUAGCUGGGAUUACAGGCACGUGCCACCACACCCAGCUAAUUUUUGUAUUUUUAUUAGAGACGGGGUUUCACAUGUUGGUCAGGCUGGUCUGGAACUCCUGACCUCAUGAUCCACCCACCUCAGCCUCCCAAAGUGCUGGGAUUGCAGGUGUAAGCCACUGUGCACGGACUCAUUUUUAUUUUUGUUUCUCUGAAUAAUACGGCCUUUUCCUUCUGGACACUUGAAGUUUUUCUUUUUACCACUGAUUUUUAGCACUUUGGUUAUGAUGUGCCUUGAUGUGGUUUUAUGUAUGUUUCUUUUGUUUGGGGCUUUUUGAGUUUCUUAGAUCUGUGAGUUUAUGGUUUUCAUUAUAUUAUGAAAUUUGCAGCCGUUAUUUCUUCAAAUUUUUUUUCUGCUUUCCCUUUUGCCCUUCCUGUAUUCUAGUUCAGCUGUGUUAGACCACUUGAUCGUGUUCCACAGGUUACUUAGGCUUUGUUAAUAUUUUUUCAGUCUUCACUGUGGGUACUUUUUACUGCUGUGUCUUCAAGUUAAACCAUCUUUCCUUCUGCAGGGGGUCUCAUCUGCUGUUACUCUCAGCCAAUGUGUUUUUCAUUUGAGAUACUGUACUUUUAAAAUCUUUACAGUUUCCAUUUGGGUCAGAAAAACUAUUUGUCUCCUUUCCACAUCACAUUCAUAUGAACUGUAUAUUGUUUGUUUUAACGUCCUUGUGUUCUAAUUCCAUUAUUUCUAUCAUUUGUAGAUUUAUUUCAAUUAAUUUUUCAUCUGGAUAUGGGUCUUUUUCACUUCUUCGUAUGCCUGGACAUUGUGAAUUUUAUAUUGCUGAACACUGGAUUUGCUGUAUUCCUCUAAAGACUGUCAGAUUGUAUUUGGUCACACAGAUAAGUAAUGUUUGGAUCAGUUUGAUCCUUGUGAAGCUUACUUUUAAGGUUUUUGUGGCUAGUAAUAGCGGCCUUUAAUCCUUGGACUAACUUGGCCCCCCUACUAAGGUGUUGAUCCUUCUAAGGCCCCGUGCUUUUUUCAUGGUCAGAGUGACCAGCCCUGUGGGAGCUCUGGGAAGUGUUGGCCCUAUUGCUUUCCAGUAGAUUGUUCCCUGACCUUGGGGAGACUUCCUCUCAAGCACUUGGAGAUCCGAGACUGAAAGGAACCCUUCUGCCAGACCUCCGGAGCCCUCUGCAUGCAGCCCCCGCUUCUCCAGUACUGGGUCCUGCAAAUUCUGGCUGCCUCAGCUUCCCCCAGCUCUGUUGGCUCCUCAGUGCAUUGAGACCCUUGGAUUUGGUUUCAGUGUUCUGUCCCUGAAGUAUGAAGCCUGGGAGUUGUCUCCAGGCUUUAAGUUUGGUUAGUCAUAAAAUUUACCUUCUUUUUUCCUUUCCCUGGAGGGGGAUCACAGUCUUGUGCUACUUUUUGCCCAGUGUCUAAAACUUGUUAUUUCAUGUGUAUUGUCUGGUUUUCUAGCUGUUUAUAGUGGGAGGACAGUUACUGUAGCAGUUACAACUUCAUGUUCCAAAUUGAGAGUCCUCCUGUUUAAAUUUUGUUAAUAUAGUCAGCCCUCUGUAUCUGUGGGUUCUGCAUUAUUGGAUUCAACCAACCAUGGAUCAGAAUUUUUGGAAAAGAAAAUAAUAACAAUACAAUGAUAAAACAACACACAUUCUUUAAAAAUACAGCAUAACAACAGGUUGAGUAUCCCUAAUCCAGAAAUCUGAAGUGCUCUAAAUUUUGAAACUUUUUGAGUGCCAUGAUGCUCAAAGGACAUACUCAUUUGAGCAUUUCAGAUUUUUAAAUUAGGGAUGUUGAACCAGUAAAUAUGUAAUGCAAAUAUUCCAAAAUCGGAAAAAUCCCAGAUCCAAACACUUCUGGUCUCAAGCAUUUCAGAUAAGGAAUAUUCAACUGUAUUUAUAUAGCAUUUACAUUGUAUUAGCUAUUAUAAGUAAUGUAGAGAUGAUUUAAAGUAUAUGGAAGGAUAUGUGCAGGUUAUAUGCAAAUACUGUGCCCUUUUUUUUUAUCCCUCCCUGAGACGGAGUUUCAUUCUUGUCACCCAGGCUGGAGUGCAGUGGCACAAUCUCGGCUCGCUGCAACCUCCGCCUUGCAGGUUCAAGUGAUUCUCCUGCCUUAGCCGCCCGAGUAGGUGGGAUUACAGGCGUGCACCACCACACCCAGCUAAUUUUUGUAUUUUUAGUAGAGACAGGGUUUCACCACGUUGGCCGGGCUGGUCUCGAACUCCUGACCUCAAAUGAUCCACUCAUCUCAGCCUCCCAAAAUGCUGGAAUUACAGCUGUGAGCCACUGCACCUGGCCAUUUUAUAUAAAGGACUUUAGCAUAUGUGAAUUUUGUUAUCCAAGGGGGAUCCUGGAAUCAAUCCCCCGUGGAUACCAGGAUACCAAGGGAUGAUUGUACUUUCAGUGAUUUAUCACUUUCAUUUGUCAACAGAUUUUAUGUCAAUUCUGCUUUCUACUUUGCCAGCUUUUUUUCUUUUUACUUUUUAAAAAACUGUGGUAAAAUGUAUAUAUAACAUAAAAUUUACCAUUUUAAUCGUUUUUAAAUGUACUGUCAUGUGGUAUUAUGUGUAUUCACAUUGUUGUGCAGUCAUCAUCACUGUUUACCUCCAGAACUUUUUCUUUUUUUUUUUUUUUUUUUGGAGACGGAGUCUCACUCUGUCGCCCAGGCUGGAGUGCAGUGGCAUGAUCUCAGCUCACUGCAACUUCUGCCUCCUGGGUUCAAGCGAUUCUCCUGUCUCAGCCUCCCGAAUAACUGGGACUAUAGGUGCCUGGCGCCAUGCCCGGCUGUUUUUUUUUGUGUUUUAGUAGAGACAAGGUUUCACCAUGUUGCCUAGGCUGGUCUUGAACUCCUGAGCUGAGGCAAUCUGCCCGCCUCCGCCUCCCAAAGUUCAUCUUCUUAAACUGAAACUCUGUACUUAUUAAACAGCAACCUUCAUUUUCCUCUCACUGAGCCCCUGGCAGCCACCAUUCCACUGUCUAUGAAUUUGACUGCUCUAGCUAGGUCACAUAAAUGGAAUCCUUUAUUUGUCCUUUUGUGACUGGCAUACUUCACUUAUCAUGUCUUCAGGGUUCAUCCCUGUUGUAGCAUGUAUCAGAAUUUAAGAAUUAACUUUUUUUUUUAAAGCUGAGUAAUAUUUGAAUGUAUAGAUAGGCCACAUUUUUCUUACCCAUUCUUUCAUCACUGGGCAUGGGUUGCUUCCACCCUUUGGCUAUUGUGAAUAAUGCUGCUGUGAACAUUGCUGUACAGACAUCUCUCAAGACUCUGCUUUCUGUUCUUCCCAGUUUGAUUUUUGCAUUUAUCUUUGUAUCUUUUUUCUUUCUUUUUUUCUGAGACCGAGUUUCACCCUUGUUGCCCAGGCUGGAGUGCUCAAUCUCUGCUUACCGUGACCUCUGCCUCCCGGGUUCAAGUGAUUCUCCUGCCUCAGCCUCCCGAGUAGCUGGGAUUACAGGCAUGCGCCACCACGACCAGCUAAUUUUGUAUUUUUAGUAGAGAUGGGGUUUCUCCAUGUUGGUCAGGCUGGUCUCAAACUCCUGACCUCAGGUGAUCCACCCGCCUCAGCCUCCCAAAGUGCUGGGAUUACAGGCAUGAGCCACUGCACUUGGCCCUUUUUUUUCUUUAUUACUUUGCUUUUAUUCUGAAUCUGAAGAUGUGUUCUUUUUUCCAUGUUGACAAUAUAAUUUAAAACUGAACGUUUCUUUUACGGUCUGCAUCCUUUACAGUAAGCUAAACAUUUUUGGUUACAUUUGUUGAAAACAGUAUGAAAGAUUCAAUGGCUUUAUGUCACUGACAAAUUUUCAUUUUGGACAACAUGCUAGUGUGAGUAGUUUCUGGUCCAGUGAAAUCCAGUUUUCAGAUAUUCCUAUUUUUGGAUUCUCAGCUGUGUAUUUGAAAUCAUCACAUUUGAAAUUUGUUUGUUCCAGAACAUAUAUGUUCUCAUUCUUGUUUGUACUUGAGUCAUGUUUAAUCACAUAUAUUUGUAGUAUGCUUAGAUGUAGUAGUUUCCAUUUUCAUAACUACUUUUCUGUUGAUCCAUUAUGGUGAAUUGCAGCUACAAAGUCAUACUGUGUAGUAGCGAAAAUGCUAACAUAAGAAGUAAAUAGUAGCAAGCAAAGGAUUUUUAAAAUAUCCAACCUAGUCAUAUAUACCCGUUUAGCUCAGUAGUUCUCAGCUGUGGUAAUACCAUUCUCUGGUGUGCAUUUUUGAAAUUCAUGAGAACAUUUUUGUUUGGCACCAUAGUAGAGGUCGUUACAGGCAUUUAAUGGACAGGGUUUAGGUCUGCUAGAUGUCUUGCAGUGUGCAGGAAAGUGCUACAGCGAAUAACUAUUCUGUCUCAUAUGGUGUUUGAAGCUCCUUUAAUUAAGUCUAAAAUAUUUUACAUAUAAACACAAAUCAUUUUUUACAUGAUAAACUACAUUUUCUAUGAAUGGCACUGUUGUGUAAAUCAAGGAGUGAGUAAUGUUUUUUCAUUUAAGGCUUUACCAAGAGUUUGCCAUUUUGGUAGAAUGCAUCACCUACAGCAGUACUCCUCAUGGUAUCGUAGUCACCAUUCGACACACCUGAUUCAGUCUGCAUUUGUUGCUGUCACAUUCAUGGUGAUGUUUCAAAUUGAUGCAAGCAUUUUAUUAUAUCAUGUUAUUUCCUAGUGUAUUGGUGCUCGAGUUUUAAUAUAUUAAAUAGUGUUUUAUUAUGAAUCAGCUUCCUUUUCUUUAUUCCCCAUAUUAUAGUUAGGACAUUGUAAUUUUUUAAGUUAUGUAGACUAUUAAUAUAAUUUCAAUAUAAUGAAGAGACUUAAAAUUUUUCAUUAUGAACAGAUGUUAGGUGUGGUAAACUUGGGAGCCAGUGAAUUGACUGAAUUAUAGCAGUCGCUAUGGCACCUCCACAGCCUUUAAGAUUACUUCAGUAUUUCUGUGAAAAGUUAUUAAUAUUACACUUCAGAUGUAUAUGAAAAUAUUAUUUUAUUGAUUUUCCUUAGAAAUUACCACACCAUUGGCCGGGCAUGGUGGCUUACCCCUGUAAUCUCAGCACUUUGGGAGGCCGAGGUGGGUGGAUGACGAGGUCAAGAGAUUGAGACCAUCCUAGCCAACUUGGUGAAACCCCGUCUCUACUAAAAAUACAAAAAUUAGCUGGGCAUGGUGGCAUGCGCCUGUAGUCCCAGCUACUUGGGAGGCUGAGGCAGGAGAAUCGCUUGAACCCAGGAGGUGGAGGUUUCAGUGAGUCAAGAUUGUGCCACUGCACUCUAGUGACAGAGUGAGAAUCCGUCUCAAAAUAAAUAAAUACAAAUAAAACAAAAACAAAAAAAAAGAAAAAAGAAAUUACUACACCAUCUAUCUGUUGACCACUUGACAAGUGAUUGGGUGAUACUGGUGGUCCGUGGACUACACUUUGAAAAGCAGUGCCACAUAUCCUGUAUUGCUUUUGUAUUAACCUUGUUGUCCUCAAUUACUGAAUUUGCUCUGUACUCCACUUUAUCAGAUACCAUUUUUUCCCUAACAUUUUUUUUUUUUAUUUUGCAGUGACAGGGUCUUGCUCCGUCACCCAGGCUGGAGUGCAGUGGCAUGAUCAUGGCUCACUGCACCCAUGACCUCCCAGGCUUAAGGGAUCCUUCUGCCUCAUCCUCCUGAAUGGCUGGGAUUAUAGGUACACACCACCAUGCUUAAUUUAUUUUUUGUAAAGAUGAGGUCUCACUGUGUUGCCUGGGCUGAACUAUAAUUUUUAUACAUAGGCUGGGUGCCGUGGCCCAUGCCUGUAAUCCCAGCAUUUUGGGAGGCCAAGGCAUGCGGUUCACUUGAGGUUAGGAGUUCGAGACCAGCCUGGCCAACAUGGUGAAACCCCGUCUCUACAAAAGAUACAAAUUUAGCUGGGUGUGGUGGCAGGUGCCUGUAAUCCCAGCUACUCGGGAGGCUGAGGCAGGAGAAUCACUUGAACCCGGGAGGUGGAGGUUGCGGUGAGCCGAGAUCAUGCCUCUCUGCACUUUAGCCUGGACAACAGAGCGAGACUCUGUCUCAAAAAAAAAUUUUUUUUUAAUACAUGAAUUGUCUAAUACCAUAGUUGUUCAACUCUAAGAUAAACUUCUUCUCAGCACCAUUAAGUAUGUAUAUAUAUAUAUACAUUUUUAAGACAGAGUCUCGCUCUGUAGCCAGGCUGGAGUGAUCUUGGCUCCCUGCAACCUCCGCCUCCCGGGUUCAAGCGAUUCCUCUGCCUCAGCCUCUCAAGUAGCUGGGACUACAGGCACGUACCAUCACACCCAGCUAGUUUUUUGUAUUUUAGUGGAGACAAAGUUUCACCAUGUUAGCCAGGAUGGUCUCGAUCUCCUGACCUUGUGAUCCACCCACCUCGGCCUUCCAAAGUGCUGGGAUUACAGGCGUGAGCCACCGCGCCCAGCUACACCAUUAAAUAUUUUUGAUGGUCCUUUGUAGUUCUUAAUGUCAAAAGAAAUUCACCAAGUGCUGUCGCAGAUGUCAUUGCCUGCAUAUAUAUAAACUUUGCCAUGCAUGGAGGUGUCUUUUCAACCAUUUAUCAUCAGAUUAAAGUUAUUUGCACUGACAACAUUACACAUGGCUGAAUUUUAAGUUACAUUUAGAUAUGUAAUUAUUUUCUGUAUCUUUCUCAAAAAGAGUGUGCUACAAGGAUUAUUUUAUAUGUAGGAAAUAGCCUGUUCCAAGAUAAAUAAUACAGUUAAAAGCAAUAGAAAUUGCUAAAUCUUAGGAGUACAUUGUAGAGUUUGAGAGAUAAUGGAGGUUACCUAUGACUGACUCAUGACUUAGGAUGGAUUAUCACUCAAGCACUAAUGUUUUAAAAAACGUUCCUUAUUUUUAAGAGAAACUGCUUAAUUUCUAGGGACAUCUAUUUGAGGAAAGAUGAAACUGAGUUUAAAGACAAAAUUCAGAGGAUUCUCAGAUGUUCUUUUAUUUGCCUCAGAAUUAUGCUGUCAGUCCCAAAGAUGUCAAAAAGAACAGAAUUCUGACUUUGAGAAGUGACAUGUUUGAUACUAUUGCAUAACUGGAGAUGGCCAAAAGUUCAGAAAAAUCACUAGACUUUGAAUGUUAAGAAAGUUUCAGUUCAAACUUUUAUCAGAUUCUGAAAAGGAAAGUGGUAUGUAACUGUUUUGAGAAAUGUAUGCUAUUAUUUUACAAUCCAUUGUGUCUUAGAAUAGAAGAAAUACAUUAUUUCUCCGUUUUAAAUUCUUUCCUUUUUUUGAACAUGCCUUUUUCAGGAUAAACUUUGCCAUGUGUGGAGGUGUCUUUUCAAGGGCCUAUUCCCUGGUGGAUUCCAGUCAAGUGUCUACAUUUCUGAUUUCCAUUCUUCUUAUAGUCUAUGGUAGUUUCAGGUCCCUUAAUAUGGACUUUGAAAAUCAAGAUAAGGAGAAAGACAGUAAUAGUUCUUCUGGGUCUUUCAAUGGCAACAGCACCAAUAAUAGCAUCCAAACAAUUGACUCUACCCAGGCUCUGUUCCUUCCAAUUGGAGCAUCUGUCUCUCUUUUAGUAAUGUUCUUCUUCUUUGACUCAGUUCAAGUAGUUUUUACAAUAUGUACAGCAGUUCUUGCAACGAUAGCUUUUGCUUUUCUUCUCCUCCCGAUGUGCCAGUAUUUAACAAGACCCUGCUCACCUCAGAACAAGAUUUCCUUUGGUUGCUGUGGACGUUUCACUGCUGCUGAGUUGCUGUCAUUCUCUCUGUCUGUCAUGCUCGUCCUCAUCUGGGUUCUCACUGGCCAUUGGCUUCUCAUGGAUGCACUGGCCAUGGGCCUCUGUGUCGCCAUGAUCGCCUUUGUCCGCCUGCCGAGCCUCAAGGUCUCCUGCCUGCUUCUCUCAGGGCUUCUCAUCUAUGAUGUCUUUUGGGUAUUUUUCUCAGCCUACAUCUUCAAUAGCAACGUCAUGGUGAAGGUGGCCACUCAGCCGGCUGACAAUCCCCUUGACGUUCUAUCCCGGAAGCUCCACCUGGGGCCCAAUGUUGGGCGUGAUGUUCCUCGCCUGUCUCUGCCUGGAAAACUGGUCUUCCCAAGCUCCACUGGCAGCCACUUCUCCAUGUUGGGCAUCGGAGACAUCGUUAUGCCUGGUCUCCUACUAUGCUUUGUCCUUCGCUAUGACAACUACAAAAAGCAAGCCAGUGGGGACUCCUGUGGGGCCCCUGGACCUGCCAACAUCUCCGGGCGCAUGCAGAAGGUCUCCUACUUUCACUGCACCCUCAUCGGAUACUUUGUAGGCCUGCUCACUGCUACUGUGGCGUCUCGCAUUCACCGGGCCGCCCAGCCCGCCCUUCUCUAUUUGGUGCCAUUUACUUUAUUGCCACUCCUCACGAUGGCCUAUUUAAAGGGCGACCUCCGGCGGAUGUGGUCUGAGCCUUUCCACUCCAAGUCCAGCAGCUCCCGAUUCCUGGAAGUAUGAUGGAUCACGUGGAAAGUGACCAGAUGGCCGUCAUAGUCCUUUUCUCUCAACUCAUGGUUUGUUUCCUCUUAGAGCUGGCCUGGUACUCAGAAAUGUACCUGUGUUUAAGGAACUGCCGUGUGACUGGAUUUGGCAUUUAAAGGGAGCUCGUUUGCAGGAGAGAGGUGCUGGAGCCCUGUUUGGUUCCUUCUCUUCCUGCGGAUGUAGAGGUGGGGCCCCUUCCAAGAGGGACAGGCCUCUCCCCAGCGCGCCUUCCUCCCACGUUUUUAUGGAUCUGCACCAGACUGUUACCUUCUGGGGGAGAUGGAGAUUUGACUGUUUAAAAACUGAAAACAGCGAGGAGUCUUUCUAGAACUUUUGAACACUAAAAGGAUGAAAAAAAUUAGCAAACCGAAGUUUCUUCAAUGACCCCUCGAGAACUUUGGGACCAGUUUCCUAUAGGGGACUCAGUUUCAGAGAACUGAGACAGAAGCUCUUCUGUCGUUAUAUUCUUCUUUCCUUUUUUUGGAUUUAUUAAAUAUUUUCUGUGGUGUGAAGUGACUUAUUAAAUCCACAGACAUUGAGUGACUUCUUACAACAUCCACAUAAGAAUUUGUUGUAAUGAGUUCAUGUCCACCCAGAUGUUGUGUUGGCAGUGAACAAGGGCACGGUUUUUAUACAUACGUACAUAUAUAUAUAUAAACACACACAUAGAUAUAUAUGAAUAAACAAAAAUGAAAUCCUGCUAAGAUCACGCUGUGUAGCUGACAGGGGCUUGCUGUCGUUUUGAGCAUGUCGAGCAGUUUACUGUGGCUUCCUUGUAUAUGGAUAAGCUGCUGUCCUUCCCCUUCACAACUGACCCCGCAGUUACAAACUAGUAUAGCAUUUGUGCUGAUUGAUGAUAGACUCAUGGACUUCAGGAGCCCUUACUUGGUUUUGAUCAGUGUAGCAAAUUAGGGAUGAAGAGUUCAAACCUUUUGGCCCUUUCUUUCUUUUCUAGGCUUCUCCCUCGCAGGGUGUUCCGUAGUUUCUUCUCGAGCCAAUGCAUGUAUUAUAGCAGCAGGUGUCUUUGUGCUUUCUCAUCAUAGUAACGUACUACUUGUAAAUACAUUUUUCUAUUUUCUAUUUUUUUGUAUUUUUUUUUUUGACAUUUUGUUUCAUUGGUGUGCUGUAUAUUUUCCAUGCCCUCACUCCUUUAAGAAAAAAAAAAAGGAAAAAAGCAACACAAUCCUGUCCUUGCUGUUGUGAUUAUAGUCUUGGUUUACCUGUGGUGACAACCGGGUGUUGGGGACACAUGUCAAAUGCCCCUCUGAGAUGGGCCCUAAAUUCCAGUAACUGGGGAAAGAACCAGCUGCUGUGUCCUGAGAGCCUGGCCCUGUGCUGUGGUCUCUGCUGCAAGCCCAGAUUUCUGGGAGUAACUAGUGUUAGGUCUGCUGACCUUUACCUAAGCAGCCCCUGCCUGGUAAGAAGGUGCCCAUUGUUCAGAGGCAAAGAGAAGCCUGCGGUUGGCAUGAGGAUGCCUGACAACAAAGGCUGGAGAAGGGCCCUGAGUUCCAGCCUCUCCCCAAGGGUCCCCGCCCCAGUGGCUGCCUCUGUCUUGACCUGUGUAAUGAAUUAGUGUGCUGUGUCACUGUGGCUUGAAGUCACUGUGGAUCGAGCUCACAGGGGGCACCCAUCCUGUUGUCAACAGAGUCUGAAGCAGUCAGGGUGUUGGAUUCCUCUGUUGUUGUCAUCAAUUCCUGCUGAGGGGUUUCUGGGGUUUUGUUUUUAAUAAAUGACUCCUUUGUAGCCUUUGUCACAUAAUCUUCACUUUGGUUGUUGGUACCAAACAGAGCUCCCAGCCAUCUCCUCCCUGUUCUGGAAGACUGAUGGGAAGACUCUGUCUGUCCCCAGACCUGGUCAUCUGCAGCUCUGGCCCAGUCAUAGAUACAUCAAAGAACUGAAGCUUCUGCUGUCCACAGAACUCAAAACUGCCUCUGCAUUGGGUGAAGACUAAAAAUCCACUUGCGGACUCUCCCUUCCUUCCUUCUCAGCCCUCGAGGAUGCAUAUAGCUAAUUAAGCAGGCCCAGAGACAGAGAGGGGGGCUCCAAAAUGACUCGGAUUAAGGGCAAGUGCCAGUGAUGGGUAGAAAUAACGUUAUCCUUCAUGCCUGUAAUCCCAGCACUUUGGGAGGCCGAGGCAGGUGGAUCACAAGGUUGGGAGCUCGAGACCAGCCUGGCCAACAUGGUGAAACCCCGUCUCUACUAAAAACACAAAAAUUAGCUGGGCAUGGUGGCAGGCGCCUGUAAUCCCAGCUAUUUGGGAGGCUGAGGCAGAAGAAUCGCUUGAACCUGGAAGGCGGAGGUUGCAGUGAGCAGAGAUUGCGCCACUGCACUCAAGUCUGGGCGACAGGGUGAGACUCCAUCUCAAAAAAAAAAAAAAAAAGGAAAUGUUAUCCUGGCAGUGGGUCAUUUUAAUUUUUCUGUCUUUGUUUUCAUAAGAAAAUUAAAUUCCAGACAGAAGGAACGUC